CAAGUAAUUCAUUUUAAGUUAACUUCUAGCAUAUAAAAUGGUUGUGUUGAAACACUGUCUUCAGAAUUUUAUUUUUAAAAGAUACUAUUUUAGUAUAAAUUCACAUUUAUAGUUGAAUGCUUUUGUGAAAGAUAUUAGUCUUUAAAAUAUUUUACAGGCUGGCCUUGUUGGCUCAUGCCUGUAAUCCCAGCACUUUGGGAGGCCAAGGCAGGUGGAUCACUUGAGCCCAGGAGUUCAAGACCAGCUUGAGCAACAUAGUGAAACCUCAUUUCUACAAAAAAUACAAAAAUUACCAGGUGUGGUGGCACACAGCUGUAGUCCCUACUCAGAAGGCUGAGGUGGGAGGGUAGAUUGAGCCCAGGAGAUAGAGGCUGCAGUGAGCCAUGAUUGCACCACUGCACUCCAGCCCAAGUGCCAGAGUGAGACCCUGUUUCAAAAAAAAAAAAGUUCGACAGUUCCAAAACACAUUAAUGUUAAUUAGAGUCUGCUAAGUUGCUAUAAAUACAACAAAAAAUUCAAUGGCACAAACAAAAUAUCAGUUGCCUCUCAUGAAAAAGUCCAAGAUUAGCAGGUGCAGAUUGGAAGAGCAAAAUUGACUCAGGGAGUGGUAGAAGGAGAGCAAGGAUCCAAGGCAUGAGCCACAAUCCAUGCCUCUUACAACCCCUCACAUCUGUCAAAUAGAACCCUUGUCUGGAUGGGCCCUUGUUCUAACCCAGUGCCUGAAAUCUUGUAUCUGUUAUAUUGGUGGUUCUACAUGACUUUAUAUUUGAAAAGUUACAUUUUAGAAGUGGAUAUUUUGUAUUUUUGGUUACUAAUAUAACUGUGUGAAAGCACUAUUAAAAAUACUUUUAUUUCGUUAAAAUUACCUGUUUAUGUUUUGGUCUCCUCCACUAAUCUGUAAGCCCCUCUGAGUAGGAAACAAUACAUUCCUCACUAUACUCCAGCACUCAGCUCAGUGCAUGGGGAUUUAAAAGUAAAUUUCUUCCAGAAGUGUAGAUUCUUAGAUCCAGAUUGUGAGGAGGGGAGGAGAGAGGUAUAGGUGAGCCGGGGGCGGAAGUGGGGGCAGGAUCAUCUUAAGGAAGGAGACCACUGCUACUACUGCUGCCCUCCUCCCACCACCUUGCCUCGUUCACAAGACAGGAGGAGAGAAAAAGCAAAAAGUUGGAAAAAAAAAAAAGUAAGAUAAAUUGCCAGACAACCUUGGCACCACCACCCGGCCCUAGGAGUUAAAAAAAGUAAUAAUAAUAACAUCAACCCCUGACCUAAACUACUUGUGUUAUCUGUGAAUUCCUGACACUGUAUGAAAAAAGCAUUGUAGCCCCCAGUCACGUUUCCCACUCUUGUUUGAUGUAUCACGACCCUUUCACGUGGACCCCUUAAAGUUGUAAGCCUUUAAAAAGGCCAAAAAUUUCUUUUUCGGGGAGCUCGGCUCUUAAGACGCGAGUCUGCCGACGCUCCCGGCCGAAUAAAAACCUCUUCCUUCUUUAAUUCGGUGUCUGAGGAGUUUUGUCUGUGGCUCAUCCUGCUACAAUCUGUUUGAACAGAUCACCUGAAAGGACAGGCGACACUAACAGGUGAAGAUCUCGGGAGACCAUGACUAAGAAAAGAAUUGCUGUGAUUGGGGGAGGAGUGAGCGGGCUCUCUUCCAUCAAGUGCUGCGUAGAAGAAGGCUUGGAACCUGUCUGCUUUGAAAGGACUGAUGACAUCGGAGGGCUCUGGAGGUUCCAGGAAAAUCCUGAAGAAGGAAGGGCCAGUAUUUACAAAUCAGUGAUCAUCAAUACUUCUAAAGAGAUGAUGUGCUUCAGUGACUAUCCAAUCCCAGAUCAUUAUCCCAACUUCAUGCAUAAUGCCCAGGUCCUGGAGUAUUUCAGGAUGUAUGCCAAAGAAUUUGACCUUCUAAAGUAUAUUCGAUUUAAGACCACUGUGUGCAGUGUGAAGAAGCAGCCUGAUUUUGCCACUUCAGGCCAAUGGGAAGUGGUCACUGAAUCUGAAGGGAAAAAGGAGAUGAAUGUCUUUGAUGGAGUCAUGGUUUGCACUGGCCAUCACACCAAUGCUCAUCUACCUCUGGAAAGCUUCCCUGGAAUUGAGAAGUUCAAAGGGCAGUACUUCCACAGUCGAGACUAUAAGAACCCAGAGGGAUUCACUGGAAAGAGAGUCAUUAUAAUUGGCAUUGGGAAUUCUGGAGGGGAUCUGGCUGUAGAGAUUAGCCAAACAGCCAAGCAGGUUUUCCUCAGCACCAGGAGAGGGGCUUGGAUCCUGAAUCGUGUAGGGGACUACGGAUAUCCUGCUGAUGUGUUGUUCUCUUCUCGACUUACACAUUUUAUAUGGAAGAUCUGUGGCCAAUCAUUAGCAAACAAAUAUUUGGAAAAAAAGAUAAACCAAAGGUUUGACCAUGAAAUGUUUGGCCUGAAGCCUAAACACAGGUUCAUCAGGCAUGAAAACCUUUGGUUCCUCCGCGGUCUUCUGAGCGGUCACGUGAACGGCUUCCUGCAGGCUGGCCAUGGCGCUUCAAGUUCCCAAGGCUCCGGGCUUCGCCCAGAUGCUCAAGGAGGGAGCGAAACACUUUUCAGAAUUAGAAGAGGCUGUGUAUAGAAACAUACAAGCUUGCAAGGAGCUUGCCCAAACCACUCGUACAGCAUAUGGACGAAAUGGAAUGAAAAAAAUGGUUAUCAACCACUUGGAGAAGUUGUUUGUGACAAAUGAUGCAGCGACUAUUUUAAGAGAACUAGAAGUACAGCAUCCUGCUGCAAAAAUGACUGUAAUGGCUUCUCAUAUGCAAGAGCAAGAAGUUGGAGAUGGCACAAACAUUGUUCUGGUAUUUGCCGGAGCUCUCCUGGAAUUAGCUGAAGAACUUCUGAGGAUUGGCCUGUCAGUUUCAGAGGUCAUAGAAGGUUAUGAAAUAGCUUGCAGAAAAGCUCAUGAGAUUCUUCCUAAUUUGGUACGUUGUUCUGCAAAAAACCUUCGAGAUGUUGAUGAAGUCUCAUCUCUACUUCGUACCUCUGUAAUGUGUAAACAAUAUGGUAAUGAAGUAUUUCUGGCCAAGCUUAUUGUUCAGGCAUGCGUAUCUAUUUUUCCUGAUUCUGGCCAUUUCAAAGUUGAUAACAUCAGAGUUUGUAAAAUUCUGGGCUGUGGUAUCACUUCCUCUUCAGUAUUGCAUGGCAUGGUUUUUAAGAAGGAAACAGAAGGUGAUGUACAUCUGUCAAAGAUGCAAAAAUAGCAGUGUACUCUUGUCCUUUUGAUGGCAUGAUAACAGAAACUAAGGGAACAGUGUUGAUAAAGACUGAUGAAGAAUUGAUGAAUUUAAGUAAGGGAGAAGAAAAUCUCAUGGAUGCAUAAGUCAAAGCUAUUGCUGAUACUGGUGCAAAUGUUGUAGUAACAGGUGGCAAAGUGGCAGACAUGGCUCUUCAUUAUGCAAACAAAUAUAAUAUGAUGUUAGUGAAGCUAAACUCAAAAUGGGAUGUCCGAAGACUCUGUAAAACAGUUGGUGCUACAGCUCUUCCUAGAUUGACACCUCCUGUCCUUGAAGAAAUGGGACACUGAGACAGUGUUUACCUCUCAGAAGUUGGAGAUACUCAGGUGGUGGUUUUUAAGCAUGAAAAGGAAGAUGGCAUCAUUUCUACCAUAGUACUUCGGGGCUCUACAGACAAUCUGAUGGAUGACAUAGAAAGGGCAGUAGAUGAUGGUGUUAAUACUUUCAAAGUUCUUACAAGGGAUAAACGUCUUGUACCCAGAGGUGGAGCAACAGAAAUUGAAUUAGCCAAACAGAUCACAUCAUAUGGAGAGACAUGUCCUGGACUUGAACAGUACGCUAUUAAGAAGUUUGCUGAGGCGUUUGAAGCUAUUCCCCGUGCACUGGCAGAAAUACUCUGGAGAAAACUCUGGAGUUAAGGCCAAUGAAGUAAUCUCUAAACUUUAUGCAGUACCUCAAGAAGGAAAUAAAAAUGUUGGAUUAGAUACUGAGGCUGUAGUCCCUGCUGUAACGGACAUGUUGGAAGCUGGUGUUCUAGAUACUUACCUGGGAAAACACUGGUCUAUCAAACUCGCUGCUAAUGCUGCAGUCACUGUACUUAGAGUGGGUCAGGUAAUCAUGGCAAAACCAGAUGGUGGGCCCAAGCCUCCAAGUGGGAAGAAAGACUGGGAUGAUGACCAAAAUGAUUGAAAUUGGCUUAAUUUUUACUGUAGGUGAAGGCUGUAUUUGUAGUAGUAUUCUAAGAAUCGCGUGAUGUUUUCUUAUUCUCCUUACAUUAAGAGGUAUUUUGUGUUUGUAUUCUUGGCUGGAUGUUAUAAUAAACAUAUUGUUACUGUCAAAAAAAAAAAAGGAAACCUUUGGUCUACUAAAUAAAAAGUAUGGAAUGAA